CCUCUACCUGCUCCACCCUCAAUCCACCAGAACCAUGGGCUGCUGUGGCUGUUCCGAAGGCUGUGGCUCCGGCUGUGGGGGCUGUGGCUCCGGCUGUGGGGGCUGUGGCUCUGGCUGUGGGGGAUGUGGCUCCAGCUGCUGUGUGCCCGUCUGCUGCUGCAAGCCCGUGUGCUGCUGUGUGCCAGCCUGUUCCUGCUCCAGCUGUGGCUCCUGUGGGGGCUCCAAGGGAGGCUGUGGCUCCUGUGGGGGCUCCAAGGGGGGCUGUGGCUCUUGUGGGGGUUCUAAGGGGGGCUGUGGUUCUUGUGGCUGCUCCCAGUGCAGCUGCUAUAAGCCCUGCUGCUGCUCCUCAGGCUGUGGGUCAUCCUGCUGCCAGUCCAGCUGCUGUAAGCCCUGCUGCUGCCAGUCCAGCUGCUGUAAGCCCUGCUGCUGUUCCUCAGGCUGUGGGUCAUCCUGCUGCCAGUCCAGUUGCUGCAAUCCCUGCUGCUCCCAGUCUAGCUGCUGUGUCCCCGUGUGCUGCCAGUGUAAGAUCUGAGGCUCUGGACUCAGGUCUCAUGUGAGUCCUGCUAACCCCAUUUUCCGAAGCUGUGACCUGUCCUUCAUCGUUGAGCCCCAAACCACUGCUCAGGGUCCAUUCCUCACUAUAAGAUGAAGCCAUAUCUGCCUGCCUUUUCCUAAGGAGAGUCCACCCUAAUUAAUGUCCAUUCCCUCCUAACAAAUUCUCUUCCCAAGUCAACUGCAACUGCGGCUGAAUCACCCCUCACCCGCUAGCCUUGCCUUUGCUUGUGUAUUCAGAGGCCUGAGCUCCUGAACCCACUUGAAGUCCUGUCUUUUCCAGCUGGAGCAGCUGGGCAUGAGUGUCCCACCUGCAACAAGGUGGGCGUUUAAGAGGCUUCCUUGGAGUGGCUUUGCCUGUCCAACACUCUGCUUUAUCUUAAAUGAAAAGUUGCAAACUAAUAAAAAUACCAUGCCGACAAACUGAAACACAUAUCUUGCUGAUUUCUCUGUUGUUCGGGGUCAUUACUAUGGCUAUGGCUAUUGUUUUCUUGUUCUUGUUGUGUUUCGGACUGCGUGGGUCUGAUGCUGAUGUUGCUGGAAGGUGCUAGGAUGGGGCUGGCUGUCUCCUCUGCCUCUCAUCUCCUUCCUGGCUGACCCCUCUUUUCUCAGAACCCCUCUCUUCCUAGGUCUUUCCAGCUAUUGAUCUGAUGGAGACAGGACUGUUCCUCAGGCCAGGGCCACAGAAGCAGAAGAGGCUGCUGAAAACUCUGGGGAGUUCAGACUUGCCUCCUUUCCCUGGUCCAGGCCUCUGCCAUCUUCCUUUGGGAAGUUUUUGUAACCAACUUACUCUGAUUGUCUUUGUUGUUACACAGCCUGUUGCCUCUGUAAAUAAACACUCCUAGCACCAA